GCAUUCCCAGCUGGCGGCGGGCAGGUGGCGGCGGCGCAGAGACCCGGCGCGGGGCGGGGGGCGCGGCUUUGGUGGCGGGACUGGCGGGCGCCCCUGCCGUGUGCUCUGGAAGCCGAGGCCACCGCGGAGCCCCUCGCGCCCCCUCUGCGCUGGGACAGGGGAGCGCGCCUCGGAAAGUUCCCCGCGGCCCCGCUGCGCGAGGAGUUUGGAGCCGCGAGCGGCUGCCCCCACGCGCGACCCCAGGCUCGGCGGGCAGGUCUGGCCGCUCAGUGACCGGAGGCAGCCCACCACCGCGCUGUUUCAUCCAGGCUGCUGACCCCAGCGGCGACUCCUUCACUGGCUUCAUGUCACAGUUUGCCUGCCCCGUCCACUGGGGACAUUUGAGCUGUUUCCAGCUUCUUAGGAGUCAAGCUGCCGUGAACUUUCGCACGCUUGUCAUUUUCUGAACGUUGGCAGCCCUUUAUCUAAGGCUGAGCUGGUUGCCCACAGGGGCCCCCGCCCCAUCUCAGGGAGUGUCCACCCAGCCCUGAGCCCGUCGUGAGGGGUCAGAGAUGGCGCUGACCCCCGAGUCCCCGAGCAGCUUCCCUGGGCUGGCCGCCACUGGCAGCUCUGUGCCGGAGCCGCCUGGCGGCCCCAACGCAACCCUCAACAGCUCCUGGGCCAGCCCGACCGAGCCCAGCUCCCUGGAGGACCUGGUGGCCACGGGCACCAUUGGGACUCUGCUGUCGGCCAUGGGCGUGGUGGGCGUGGUGGGCAACGCCUACACGCUGGUGGUCACCUGCCGCUCCCUGCGUGCGGUGGCCUCCAUGUACGUCUACGUGGUCAACCUGGCGCUGGCCGACCUGCUGUACCUGCUCAGCAUCCCCUUCAUCGUGGCCACCUACGUCACCAAGGAGUGGCACUUCGGGGACGUGGGCUGCCGCGUGCUCUUCGGCCUGGACUUCCUGACCAUGCACGCCAGCAUCUUCACGCUGACCGUCAUGAGCAGCGAGCGCUACGCUGCGGUGCUGCGGCCGCUGGACACCGUGCAGCGCCCCAAGGGCUACCGCAAGCUGCUGGCGCUGGGCACCUGGCUGCUGGCGCUGCUGCUGACGCUGCCCGUGAUGCUGGCCAUGCGGCUGGUGCGCCGGGGUCCCAAGAGCCUGUGCCUGCCCGCCUGGGGCCCGCGCGCCCACCGCGCCUACCUGACGCUGCUCUUCGCCACCAGCAUCGCGGGGCCCGGGCUGCUCAUCGGGCUGCUCUACGCGCGCCUGGCCCGCGCCUACCGCCGCUCGCAGCGCGCCUCCUUCAAGCGGGCCCGGCGGCCGGGGGCGCGCGCGCUGCGCCUGGUGCUGGGCAUCGUGCUGCUCUUCUGGGCCUGCUUCCUGCCCUUCUGGCUGUGGCAGCUGCUCGCCCAGUACCACCAGGCCCCGCUGGCGCCGCGGACGGCGCGCAUCGUCAACUACCUGACCACCUGCCUCACCUACGGCAACAGCUGCGCCAACCCCUUCCUCUACACGCUGCUCACCAGGAACUACCGCGACCACCUGCGCGGCCGCGUGCGGGGCCCGGGCAGCGGGGGAGGCCGGGGGCCCGUUCCCUCCCUGCAGCCCCGCGCCCGCUUCCAGCGCUGUUCGGGCCGCUCCCUGUCUUCCUGCAGCCCACAGCCCACUGACAGCCUCGUGCUGGCCCCAGCGGCCCCGGCCCGACCUGCGCCCGAGGGUCCCAGGGCCCCGGCGUGAGCACGCGGAGGGGCGGCUGGAGUCCAGGCGGGGACGCGCCCCAAAGCCCCAGCCACUCCCGGGAGCCCCCCCAACUCCCAAAUCACAGGCCCUGCCCCUCCUCCGUCCCCUUCUGGAAAGAUCCUGCUCGCUUCCCCUCAGCGCCCUUCCCGUGAUGCCCAGAAGCGCCCACCCGCCUCCCUGAGGGUCUCCAGGAGGCUCCAGCGCAGUCCCGGCUUCUGGAGACCAUGGCUUCGUCACAGAGGGCAGCAGGCGCCAGUGCCCGGCCCGUGUGGAGACCAUGGCGCGGCUGCCGCCCCCGGGACCCUCCUCCUCUCAGCCAGCGGCCCUGUGACUCCUGUUCCUGCCUGUGUGGCUCCAUCCCUUGUGGCUUUGCCACUGGAACAAUCAACCCUGAGCUGGCUUCCGUGUCCUGCCUAGGCGCGGGGGACGCCACAUCUGAGGUGUGGGAGGAUCGGCCGGCAGGAUCCCCAGGACGACAACGGCAGCUCAAGGGGGAGCCUGUGGGUCUGGCUGGGGUAGAGGGUGCACCUGCCUUUGAGGCCUGUGCAGGCGGCUGGUCUGGCACCUGAUGUGGGGCAGGGAAGGUGGCCAGGAGGGGAGGCUCCAGCUGAGGGGUGGAGCAGGGAAGGCACUGCCCAGCAGAGGCCUGAGGCUUUGGGUGCAGAACGCAAGAGGACAAGGUCAGUGGCCGCACCUACAGGCCUCCUGGCCUCUCAUCCACGUCUGGCUCAGGUCUGAUCAGAAAGGGAAUCCAGGUCCCACCUCACAGUAGCAUUGGCAGUCUCUGCCCCACUCACCCCUCACUGCCUCCUGGACAGACUUCCUGCCCCAGCUCCCAGCUUGGCCAACCAUCCUCUCUCUGGCGACUGCCCCCCUCCAGCCCCCAGCCCGGCCCCGGACCCUGCAUGGCCUCCCCCAGCCUGGCCUCCCCUCCCCACCCCAUGGCCAUGCCCAGACUACCAGCCCCUUGGGGCUCCAUCUGAACACUGGGGCAAGGGUCAUGCCCGCUUGGUCCCUCCAGUGCCUACCCCUCAGUGGAGUGAGCACAGCUCUGCUGGCAGGACUGUGGCCGGCGUCAGGAAUAAGCAUGCAGCGCUCUCCCCAGGGCCUCCCGGAAGAGGGGCAAUGCUUGCAGCUCCCCCCUGGAGUUACGAAAGUGCUCUGGAACUAGACGCUGGUGACUGGGCGAUGCUGUGAACGAGCCAGUGCCACAGAACUGUGCACCUGAAUGUGUGAGUUCUGUCGUGUUUUACUUUAAAAACAAAAGGAUCCCACUCCCCGACCUUGUCCCUCUGUUAAAAUUGAAAGAGACUGAUGUCAGCCGCCCCGUCUGGGAGGGAGGUGGGGGGGUCAGCCCCCCGCCCGGCCAGCCACCCCGUCCGGGAGGUGAGGGGCGCCUCUGCCCGGCCACCCCUACUGGGAAGUGAGGAGCCCCUCUGCCCGGCCACCACCCCGUCUGGGAGGUGUGCCCAGCAGCUCAUUGAGAACGGGCCAUGAUGACAAUGGCGGUUUUGUGGAAUAGAAAGGCAGGAAAGGUGGGGAAAAGAUUGAGAAAUCGGAUGGUUGCCGUGUCUGUGUAGAAAGAAGUAGACAUGGGAGACUUUUCAUUUUGUUCUGUACUAAGAAAAAUUCUUCUGCCUUGGGAUCCUGUUGAUCUAUGACCUUACCCCCAACCCUGUGCUCUCUGAAACAUGUGCUGUGUCCACUCAGGGUUGAAUGGAUUAAGGGCGGUGCAAGAUGUGCUUUGUUAAACAGAUGCUUGAAGGCAGCACGCUCGUUAGGAGUCAUCACCACUCCCUAAUCUCAAGUACCCAGGGACACAAACACUGCGGAAGGCCGCAGGGUCCUCUGCCUAGGAAAACCAGAGACCUUUGUUCACUUGUUUAUCUGCUGACCUUCCCUCCACUAUUGUCCUAUGACCCUGCCAAAUCCCCCUCUGCGAGAAACACCCAAGAAUGAUC